UCUGGCCGAGGCGCCACGCGACAGUUGAGACGCCAGAUGUGAGUUGAGGUGCCAGACGUGAGUUGAGGUGCCAGACGUGGCGGCGUUGGGUACCCAGGACCCUCGGACGGGUCUGCUGCGGCUUGCUGGGGGUCCACUCCAGACCCUGUUCGCCUGGGUAUCACCAGUGGAGUUUGCAGAACAGCAAAGAUUGCUGCUUGCUCCUUCCUCCAGAAGCUUCUUCCCACAGUGGCAUCAACCUGAUUGAUGUCAGCCGGAACUCUCCUGCAUGAGGUGUCUGGCGACCCCUGAUGGGAAGUCUCACCCAGUCAAGAAGCACGGGACUGGAAGGGGGACCUCCUUACGGAGGCAGACUGACUGUCCCUUAGCAGAGCUGGUGCACUGUAUUGGAGGAAUAACCCUCCUUGGGAUCAGCUGGUCUCUUCAGAGCCAGCAGGCAGGAAAGAUUAAGUCUGCUGAACCUCGGACCAUGGCCGCCGCUCCCCCGAGGUGCUCUGUCCCAGGGAGAUUAGAGUUCUUGUCUGUAAGCCCCUGACUGUAGCUACUGGAAUUCCUGCAGGGAUGCCCUCCAGGUGAGGAGGGAUGGCUUCGGGUCCCACCUAGGAAGCAGUCUGGCCACGAUCUGCAACAGCCACUUUGCUGCGUUGUGGGGAAUUCCACCCAGUCCAAACCUCCUAGUCUCCUUAGCACUGUCAGGGGAAAACCUCCAACUAAAGCCUCAGUAAUGACGGUCGCCCCUCCCCCUGGGAACUGAGUUGUCCCAGGCGGACUCCAGACUGCUGUGCCGGCAGCGGGGAUUUCAAGCCAGUGGUUCUUAGCUUGCGGGGUUUCCGUGGGAGUGGGACCCUCUGAGCGAGACCACUUGGCUCCCUGGCUACAGCCCCCUUUCCACAGAAGUGGACAUUUCUCCUGCCUCACUGGAGUUCCAGGUGCUGCCGGAGUAUGUAAAAAUUCCUGCAGCUCAGUGCCUGCCCAAACAGCCGCCGACGGGAGCAGCUGUCAUUGGUCUGCCCAGUUUUGUAUUUGAGACCCAGGGCACUGGUGGUUGUAGGCUCCCGAGGGGAUCUGCUGAUCUGUGGAUUGCAAAAAUCUGUGGGAAAAGCUUAGUACCCUUGGUGGGUAGCACUGUCCCUCACCACUUCCCUUGGCUGGGGAGGGAGGUCCCCCUGCCCUGUGCAGUUCCUGGGUGAAGCAAUACCCUGCUUCUUCUCGCUCUCUGUGGGUCAUGCCGACCAUCUAGUCAGUCCCAGUGAGAUGAACUGGGUAUCUCAGUUGGAAAUGCAGAAAUCACCCACAUUCCUCGUUCCUCUCGCUGGCAGCUGCAGACCAGAGCUGCUUCUAGUCGGCAGUCUUGGCCCCUCCCCGCCGAGUCAACUGACCCACUGGGAAUGUGACCUUGUGAAUCACCCAGAAAUGAGGUACAGGGGAGAGAAACACCUACUUGGAAAGCACCGAAACAACUGAAUUGGAAAAUGUGGAAAGGGGAUUGGGGGAGGGGACUCUUUCUGAGAUCUGGCUCCAGUACUAACAGCAAAGGGAACUUGGGCAAGUUACAGACUCUCUGUGCCUUGGUUUUGUCAUCAGCAAAACAGAAUCAUCCCAUAAACUGUAAGGUCCGUGGUAUCAGAGGGUCCCCAGUCUGACUGCACAUCUAAGUCGUUAACAAACACAUUCCAGGCCCCAACUGAGCGCACUGAAUCAGAAUCCCUGCAAGGAGGACAAUGAUCUUGUAUUUGCACUGACCUUCCAGAUGUUUCUUACUCUGAUCAACUUGGGGGUAGGAACCAUUGAGCUGCAUCACAUCAUUCCAAAGCCCAAACACAGAAGCAGAACAAGAAUAUAUUCAAUGCAUUCUCUAAAGUGGAGAAAACUGUUGAGGGAACCUAGAAGUGAAGGAAACCUGGCUUGCUGGGCUCCAUCUUAACUUUAUCCUGAGUACGGCAGAGACAGGAGCACUUUGGGACACAUGCCUGAGGUAGUGACAGUCCAACAUUGAAACAGUGGAAGCCCUAGUUUCAAAUUCAAACUUGCUUUGAGUAGAAAUUAAGUUUACAUCUUUUUGCAUAGCAACAGGGCCAGUUUUCUCCAAGCUGCUCAAUUUACAAGAAAAGAAAUCAUAUGGCUAAGAAUUCAAACUUCAGCAGACAUGGGUAAACAAGGAACUCUUACAAAUCUAUUCUAGCAACCUAACAAGAAACCAGAAAUUUAGCAAGUUCUUUCCCGCUCAGGACAAUUGUGUUCACUAGAUCAGAGGCACUGAGACAUGAAGAAAAGACCCGCUAAAAAGGGAAAGCCUUCCUUCCUGCCCUAGGACAUCCCUGCCAACUUCAGGGAGGUGGGAACCCAGCUGCGCUCUCUACAGUAUGGGUUACUUUUGUGUCUGGAAGGUGUCUGACAUCCUGAGACCUGGACCCAUUUCAAGGAGCUUUGGGAAGAGCCCAGAUCACUGAUGGAAUUGGACAGUGCGUGGAAAUGGUUCAGCAGGACGAGGACCGUUACCUGGUACGCUGGCUGCUACCUCCCUCACUCUUGUCAGAGUCGGAGCUACAGGCAGUGCCUUCAGCUCUGAGCUCAGGCAUCCCGGUCCCUGUUUUUGCGGUUAAGGACUCUAAAGUGUUGUGUCGUGUUCAUCAACUUUUUCUCAACUUCCCUGGCUCUACCUCUUCUGCCACAAACGUCAGCAUGGUGGUAUCUGCCGACCCUUUGUCCAGCGAGAGGGCAGAGAUGAACAUCCUAGAAAUCAACCAGGAAUUGCGCUCGCAGCUGGCAGAGAGCAAUCAGCAGUUCCGAGACCUCAAAGAGAAAUUCCUUAUAACUCAAGCUACUGCCUACUCCCUGGCCAACCAGCUGAAGAAAUACAAGUGUGAAGAGUACAAAGACAUCAUAGACUCUGUGCUGAGGGAUGAACUGCAGUCCAUGGAGAAGCUGGCAGAGAAGCUCAGGCAAGCUGAGGAGCUCAGGCAGUAUAAAGCCCUGGUUCACUCUCAGGCAAAAGAGCUGACCCAGUUACGGGAGAAGUUACGGGAAGGGAGAGAUGCCUCCCGCUGGCUGAACAAGCAUCUGAAAACCCUCCUCACUCCUGAUGACCCUGACAAGUCCCAGGGUCAGGACCUCCGAGAGCAGCUGGCUGAGGGGCACAGGCUGGCAGAGCACCUUGUUCACAAGCUGAGCCCAGAAAAUGAUGAAGAUGAAGAUGAGGAUGAAGACGACAAAGACGAGGAGGUUGAGAAAGUACAGGAAUCACCUGCCCCCAGAGAGGUGCAGAAGACUGAAGAAAAGGAAGUCCCUCAGGACUCACUGGAGGAAUGUGCUGUCACUUGUUCAAAUAGUCACAACCCUUCUAACUCCAACCAGCCUCACAGGAGCACCAAAAUCACAUUUAAGGAACACGAAGUCGACUCUGCUCUGGUUGUAGAGAGUGAACACCCUCAUGAUGAAGAGGAGGAAGCUCUAAACAUUCCCCCAGAAAAUCAAAAUGACCAUGAGGAGGAGGAGGGGAAAGCGCCAGUGCCCCCCAGACACCAUGACAAGUCCAACUCUUACCGGCAUCGUGAAGUCUCUUUCUUGGCAUUGGAUGAACAGAAAGUUUGCUCCGCUCAGGAUGUUGCCAGGGAUUACUCCAAUCCCAAAUGGGAUGAAACCUCACUUGGCUUCCUCGAAAAGCAAAGUGAUCUUGAAGAGGUGAAAGGACAAGAAACAGUUGCUCCCAGGCUCAGCAGGGGACCGCUGAGAGUGGACAAGCAUGAAAUCCCCCAGGAGUCACUGGAUGGAUGUUGCUUGACUCCUUCCAUCCUUCCUGACCUGACUCCCUCCUACCACCCUUAUUGGAGCACUUUGUACUCUUUUGAAGACAAGCAAGUCAGCUUGGCUCUUGUAGACAAAAUUAAAAAGGAUCAAGAGGAGAUAGAAGACCAAAGCCCACCAUGCCCCAGGCUCAGCCAGGAGCUGCCAGAGGUGAAGGAGCAGGAAGUCCCAGAGGACUCUGUGAAUGAAGUUUACUUGACUCCCUCAGUUCACCAUGACGUGUCUGACUGCCACCAGCCUUAUAGCAGCACCUUGUCCUCAUUGGAGGAUCAGCUUGCCUGCUCUGCUCUGGAUGUAGCCUCCCCCACCGAGGCGGCCUGUCCCCAAGGGACUUGGAGUGGAGACUUGAGCCACCACCAGUCAGAGGUGCAAGUUUCACAGGCACAGCUGGAACCAAGCACCCUGGUGCCCAGUUGUCUGCGACUACAGCUGGAUCAAGGGUUCCACUGUGGGAACGGCUUGGCCCAGCGGGGCCUUUCCUCCACCACCUGCAGCUUCUCAGCCAAUGCUGAUUCUGGGAACCAAUGGCCCUUCCAAGAGCUGGUUUUAGAGCCCUCUCUGGGGAUGAAGAACCCUCCCCAGCUGGAAGAUGAUGCACUUGAAGGCUCAGCAAGCAACACACAAGGGCGUCAAGUCACUGGCCGGAUUCGUGCCUCCCUUGUCCUGAUACUGAAGACCAUCAGAAGAAGACUCCCGUUCAGCAAGUGGAGACUGGCAUUCAGAUUCGCUGGCCCGCAUGCUGAGAGCGCAGAGAUACCAAAUACUGCUGGAAGGACGCAAAGGAUGGCAGGAUGAAAGAAUGUCACAAAAAGCAGCUUUUCCACUUGAUAAAAACAACUAAAACAGCAAAGCAAGUUUAAGUCCAAACACAAUACUGCAGGGGUCCUUCACUGAGGAUUGAAUUUCAGACACAGAAUACUCUUGAUGACUUCAAGCCACUAUGCUCCUUUGAUUUGAGAAGCCACAUUCCAUCCCCCUCCAAUUGUGAUCAAUACCUAGGGAGACCAAUGCCCAGAUGGACAAAUAGCAUUGACCGGCGUUAGCCCUGUUUCUCAAUUCCCAUCGUGUAGAGAACAGGAGUCCGCAGCUGCUGGCAGGAGACAGCAUGUCAGCCGGGACUCUGCCAGGGCAGAGUAUGAGCAAUGCCAUGUUCUUGCUGAAAACGCUUAGCCUGAGUUUCAUAGGCGGUAACCCUCAGAUAACUGCAGAAUGUAGAACAUUGAACAGGACAACUGACCUGUCUCCUUCAAACAGUCCAUGUCACCACCAAGAACACAACAAAAAGGAGAAGAGACAUUUUGAGUUCAAAAAGAGUAAAAAGCCUAUGCAGCUUAUGCUUUUUUAGUCAUUUUGAACCCAAAACAUCUCCUCAUCUUUUUGUUGUUGUCAUUGAUGGUGGUGACAUGGACUUGUUUGUGGAGGACAGGUCAGCUGUCUGGCUCAAUGGUCUACAUUCUGAAGUUAUCUGAAAAUGUCGUCAUGAUUAAAUUCAGCCUAAACAUUUUGCCAGGAACUCUGCAGAGUCCAUGCUGUGAGCUUCCUACCUCAGCCCAUCUGCAGGCAGAGAAGGCCCAGUGUGUCCAUCCCCAGUGCGGUGAUACUAGGAUGGUCACUUGGUUAAGGAGGGGUCUAGGAGCUCUGUCCCUUGUAAAGACAUCUUAUUUGUAAGUAAUUUGGAAAGUGGUUUGAAAUAGUAUAAAUAUCCUGUAUUCUAGUGAUCUUCUUCAGAACAUUUUAUCACCAAUUAAUCACCCCGUCUGUGUCAGUUAUUAUAUUUAAGUUUGUACAUUGAAAAUUGUCUAUCUCAAAAUCUUACCUUAUACUUGCUUUUGCUGGCAUUCUUUGUAAAAAAGAUCAUUCCCUGCCCAAAUUUUAACUUUCAUCCAAAAUUAAUUUUAAUUUCUUUUUGCUGGCAUUCUGUUGUGAAAAAGAAUAUUCUCUGCCCCAAUUAUAACUUUCAUCCAAAAUUAAUUUUAGUCCAUCAGUUAAAAUUUUAAAUUUUAAAUCUGUUUAAUUAAAACAUUUCUUGCCUCUCA